ACUGUGUGCCCAUCACGCGUGGUGUCCACUGCCAGCUGCCCCUGUGAGUCCCUGUCCUUGCUUGGAGCCUGCUGCUUGUCUCAGAUCCUUGGACCCAGCCCUGACCCCAGUCCAGCUAAGCUCAACCCUGACCGGUCCUCCUUCGAGACUCUUUCAGCCUAAGAUCUCCAACCAGACCUGCCCGCCAUGUCGGCUGCGCCCGGCCUCCUGCACCAGGAGCUGUCCUGCCCGCUGUGCCUGCAGCUGUUCGACGCGCCCGUGACAGCCGAGUGCGGCCACAGUUUCUGCCGCGCCUGCCUAGGCCGCGUGGCCGGGGAGCCGGCGGCGGAUGGCACCGUUCUCUGCCCCUGCUGCCAGGCCCCCACGCGGCCGCAGGCACUCAGCACCAACCUGCAGCUGGCGCGCCUGGUGGAGGGGCUGGCCCAGGUGCCGCAGGGCCACUGCGAGGAGCACCUGGACCCGCUGAGCAUCUACUGCGAGCAGGACCGCGCGCUGGUGUGCGGAGUGUGCGCCUCACUCGGCUCGCACCGCGGUCAUCGCCUCCUGCCUGCCGCCGAGGCCCACGCACGCCUCAAGACACAGCUGCCACAGCAGAAACUGCAGCUGCAGGAGGCAUGCAUGCGCAAGGAGAAGAGUGUGGCUGUGCUGGAGCAUCAGCUGGUGGAGGUGGAGGAGACAGUGCGUCAGUUCCGGGGGGCCGUGGGGGAGCAGCUGGGCAAGAUGCGGGUGUUCCUGGCUGCACUGGAGGGCUCCUUGGACCGCGAGGCAGAGCGUGUACGGGGUGAGGCAGGGGUCGCCUUGCGCCGGGAGCUGGGGAGCCUGAACUCUUACCUGGAGCAGCUGCGGCAGAUGGAGAAGGUCCUGGAGGAGGUGGCGGACAAGCCGCAGACUGAGUUCCUCAUGAAAUACUGCCUGGUGACCAGCAGGCUGCAGAAGAUCCUGGCAGAGUCUCCCCCACCCGCCCGUCUGGACAUCCAGCUGCCAAUUAUCUCAGAUGACUUCAAAUUCCAGGUGUGGAGGAAGAUGUUCCGGGCUCUGAUGCCAGCGCUGGAGGAGCUGACCUUUGACCCGAGCUCUGCGCACCCGAGCCUGGUGGUGUCUUCCUCUGGCCGCCGCGUGGAGUGCUCGGAGCAGAAGGCGCCGCCGGCCGGGGAGGACCCGCGCCAGUUCGACAAGGCGGUGGCGGUGGUGGCGCACCAGCAGCUCUCCGAGGGCGAGCACUACUGGGAGGUGGAUGUUGGCGACAAGCCGCGCUGGGCGCUGGGCGUGAUCGCGGCCGAGGCCCCCCGCCGCGGGCGCCUGCACGCGGUGCCCUCGCAGGGCCUGUGGCUGCUGGGGCUGCGCGAGGGCAAGAUCCUGGAGGCACACGUGGAGGCCAAGGAGCCGCGCGCUCUGCGCAGCCCCGAGAGGCGGCCCACGCGCAUUGGCCUUUACCUGAGCUUCGGCGACGGCGUCCUCUCCUUCUACGAUGCCAGCGACGCCGACGCGCUCGUGCCGCUUUUUGCCUUCCACGAGCGCCUGCCCAGGCCCGUGUACCCCUUCUUCGACGUGUGCUGGCACGACAAGGGCAAGAAUGCCCAGCCGCUGCUGCUCGUGGGUCCCGAAGGCGCCGAGGCCUGAGCCGCCGGACGGGUAGUGGAGGGGCGCGGGGGCCUGGGUUGAAGCUUAGGUCUCCUUGGUCGGGUCUGACGGGAGAAGGGUGGGGAGCGGGUUGCCAGGGCCCAGGGGGCUGGGAACUGGGGGAUCUCCCAGAAUACUGACAAGCGUGGGGUAGGACUGGCUUGGUGGCUCAUGCCUGUAAUCCCAGCACUUUGGGAGACGGAGGCGGGUGGAUCACCUGAGGUCAGGAGUUCAAGACCAGCCUGGCCAACAUGGUGAAACUCCUCUCUACUGAAAAUACAAAAAUGAGCUGGGCGCGGUGGCAUACGCCUGUAAUCCCAGCUAGUUGGGAGGCUGAGGCAGGAUAAUUGCUUGAACCCAGGAGGUGGAGGUUGCAGUGAGCAGACAUUGCGGCACUGCACUCUAGCCUGGGUGACAAGAGUGAGACUCUGUCUCAAAAAAAAAAAAAAGUGUGGGGGUUGGCAUGGCCUGGGGACUGCUGGUGAGGGGUUGGAGUGACGCUGGGGACAAGACCCAGUGGGGUAGGGAGAUCUGGAGUCAGGUCAGUGGGGAAAUCAGAAUUUGGGAACCAGGAGGCCUGAGAAUUCCAGGAAGAAACUAAGGUUGAGCGAGGGAGGGACAGGGCCAGGUUGGGGGAUUGAUGGGAGGAGCUUGAGAACCUGUAGAUAAGGGGCUCCUUUUGCCUCACACUCCCCUCCUCCUUAGGCCUUGGGUCCCCCGCUCCAGAUUCACCUUACCCAAAAGCCUUCUCCUUAGUUCUCCACCUUAGGCAUGCAUUAAAAUCACCUUUUUAAAGCCCUUAGCCAUGACUUGUUAAAGCAUAGGGUGCUAAGUUUCUGAUUUAGUAGGUUGGACAGGUCAAAAAUGCUCAUUUCUUUUUUUUAUUUCUUUUUUUUUUUUUUUUUUUUUUUUUUGAGACAGAGUCUUGCUCUGUCACUCAAGGCUAGAGUGCAGUGGUGCCAUCUCGGCUCACUGCAACCUCUGCCUCCAGGGUUCAAGCAAUUCUCAUGCCUCAGCCUCCCAAGUAGCUGGGACUACAGACGCCCGCCACCACACCUGGCUAUUUAUUUUUAUUUUUAGUAGGGGUUUCACUAUGUUGGCCAAGCUGGUCUCGAACUCCUGACCUCAAGUGAUUCACCCGCCUUGGCCUCCCAUAGUGCUGGGAUUACAGACAUGAGCCACUGCACCUGGCUGAAAAUGCUCAUUUUUUUUUUUUUAAUUUAGUUUUUGUAGAAAUGGUGUCUCGUUACAUUGCCCAGGCUGAUCUUGAACUCUUGGCCUCAGGUGAUCCUCCUGCCUUGGCCUUCCAAGUGCUGGGAUUACAGGUGUGAGCCACCACGCCCUGCCAAAAAUGUGCAUUUCUAGCAGGUUCCCAGGUGACGCUGCUGGCCACAGGGGCUGACGCUGCGGGAAGCCCUGACCUAGUGCACAACCCAUUGGGCUCUUCACUGUCAGUGUAGAGGCAUAGGUCCAAAAUAUGUUUCCCCAGUCAAAAACAUGUAAGGUUUGCACCAGGAGUGGAAGGAAACAAACAAACAUAAACCAAAGCAAAGACACUUAAGGGCUGGGUACUCAUGCCUGUAAACCCAACACUUUGGGAGUUUGAGGCAGGAGGCUCAUUUGAGGCCAGGAGUUUGAGACCAGCCUGGGGAACAUAGUGAGACCCUGUUGCAACAAAAACCAGAAAAACAACAAAAAGAAGACAUUGGAAAAUGGCUGGAGCUGAUUCUAGGUGAAUAAACAACCCUCGACUUAACUUGCUUUGCCUCUGGGAUAUGUUUAUCGAGCGUCUUGAACGUUGAGGAAGCCAGCCAAGAGAAAGAGCCUGAUGCCAAGGUCACACUGGUCCCUGCUGCUCAUGGGGAAGAGAAGGCCCCCAACUAGAUGUCCCAGAACUGGCCGCUCCCCACUUACUUGCUGGUUCACACCUUCUUUGGUUUUAGCGCACAGGGCAUUUCUUGGGCUCUGGAGUAACCACUGAGGCCAGAGUGAGAGUCCCUCUUCCCUGGAGGGAGAGGCCUUUGGGGAUCCAGACAGGCUUCUCUCCUGAGGGAAGACGCUGGCCUGGGGUCACUCAUUUUCACGGGGAGGGUGUGCUGGCGGGAUGGGUGGAAGGGCCUGGGGCCCCGGCAGCCCAUUGCGGAGGUUUUCUCGGGAGAUGGUGGGUAUGGGACUAAGGGUGAAAGGGAAGUUGUGAGUUGGGUAAGAAAGGCCUGAGGAUCUGGCAGGGGAAGGCGGCACACCUGGGUGUGUCUCCCAGAGGAAGGCCUGUGGAGCCCUGGCUUCAGGAGACAGAAGAGAGGAUUAACGGUAGAAGCUCUUUCAUGUUAGAAAAUAAAACAAUAUAGCUAAGGGAUUAUUUGGUUGUAAAAUCCAACACCAUUAAUAAAACUGUUAUAUUCUGACUCCUUCCUCAUUAAAUCCACAUGAAAAGACAUGUGACCUACUGCAAGGCCUCCUAAUUGCCCUCCAGCCUUUAAUCCUGACUUGGUAAUGUUUCCAAAAAUGCAAAUGUGGUCACGGGACUCAGUUGCUCAAAACUUUCAACAACUCCCUCUUGCCUACAGGAUAAAGCCCCCAGUCUUUGGCUUAGCAUUUGAGCUGUUCUGCCAUUUUUUUUGUUGGUUGGUUUGUUUGUUUUGUUUGAGACAGAGUCUCGCUCUGUCGCCCAGGCUGGAGUGCAGUGGUGUGAUCACCGUAACCUCCGCCUCCUAGGUUCAAGGGAUUCUCCUGCCUCAGCCUCCCGAGUAGCUGGGAUUACAGGUGCCCGCCAGGCUGGUCUCGAACUCCUGACCUCAGGUGAUCCACCCAUUUUGGCCUCCCAAAGUGCUGGGAUUACAGGCUGGCCUUCCAGCUUCAUCUGUUUUUAGUUAAAAAACAAUUUUUUUUUUUGAGACAAGGUCUUGCUCUGUCGCACAGGCUGGAGUGCAAUGGUGUGAUUGUGGCUCACUGCAGCCUUGACCUCCUGGGCUCACAUGAUCCUCCCACUCCAGCCUCCUGAGUAGAUAGGAUGGCAGGCACCCAUCACCAUGCCUGACUAUUUUUUAUUUUUUGUAUUUUGGUAGAGAUGAGGUCUCACUAUGUUGCUCAUGCUGGUCUCGAGCUCCUGGCCUCAAGCGAUCCUCCCAUCUUGGCUUCCCAAAGUGUUGGGAUUACAGGUGUGAGCCACUGAGCCCAGCCCAGCUUCAUCUUUUAUUUUAUUAUUAUUUUUUGAGAUGGAGUCUCACCGUGUCACCCAGGUUAGAGUGCAGUGGUGUGAUCUUGGCUCACUGCAACCUCUGCCUCCCAGGUUCAAGUGAUCCUCCUGCCUCAGCCUCCCGAGUAGCUGGGACUAUAGGCAGGUGACACUACGCCUAGCUGAUUUUUGUAUUUCUAGUGGGGACAGGGGCUUCACUAUGUUGGCCAGCCUGGUCUCGAACUCCUGACCUCAGGGGAUCCCCCAACUCGGCCUCCCAAAGUACUAGGAUUACAGGCUUGAACCGCCGCGCCCAGCCCCAGCUUCAUCUUAAAAAGAAAAGUUCUCUGUUUUAAUAUCUAACAGGGCAAAUAUUGAAAGAUAAAACCACAUAACAAAAGCUCUUUGGGAUCCUAGUGUUGGGGAAAGGCUGCUGUCCAUUGACUGUCACUGAACUCUCUGUCAUUGCUCAGGCUAAGGACUGGCCACAGUGAGGGAGGGACCUGUGGUCUCCUGUGUUGCUCCUCACCCUGUAGACUGUGGGCUGUGGGCUGUGUCCAGCCUCACCUUGGAUCACCGCCCUGUGCAUGUCUACACUCUGGCUAUGCUGAACUGAACUGCUGGGGUCUCUGCACCUCCUUUUUUUUUUUUUUUUUUUUGAGAUGCAGUCUUGCUCUGUCGCCCAGGCUGGAGUGCAAUGGUGCUAUCUCAGCUCACUGCAACCUCUGCCUCCCAGGUUCAAGUGAUUCUCCUGCCUCAGCCUCCGCAGUAGCUAGGAUUACAGGCACCCACCACCACGCCAGGUUAGUUUUUUCAUUUUUAUUUGUAUUUUUAGUAGAGGCGGGGUUUUGCCAUGUUGGCCAGGCUGAUCUCGAACUCCUGACCUCAAAUGAUCUGCCCGCCUCAGCCUCCCAAAGUGCUGGGAUUACAGGCAUGAGCUGUCGGGCCUGGCCCCUGCACUUCUUUUUUAGGAAUGUCAGUUCCCUCCCACUUAUCCUUCAUGGCUCUCCCAAAACACCACCAUUUCCUGUCCUCUCUUGACCUUCUAGGCCUCCAGGAAGAAUCAGUUACUCUCCUCUCUGGAUCGCCCAGCAGCUCCUCCACCAUGUGUAGCCCACGGCAUUGAAUUGUCUACACACAGGCCAUGGUGUCUGGAGGGAUGGUGGUAUCUGAGACCCAAAGCCUCCUUCUGAGGAAAUGGGUACUCUGAGAAGCAGAUGCCAAGAUAGGAUUAAAUGGGCAGAGAUUUUAGGAGGGAAGAUGCCCAUGUGAGGGAAGAUGGGGAGGGCCAUCAGACCGUGUCGCAAGUCUGCUGUUCGUGUGGGAGGGAGGGAGGGAAGGCUCUUGUGGCGUCUCCGGCAGCCAGAGCCACCGUCCAAACACUCCUGUGCCUUCCGGGACCCGGGCUGGCUUUAGUCUCCCUGCAGAGCUGAGUAAUGUAUGCUGCCUUUUGUUGGAAUUAUAUCAGGAAACUUUCUUUCGAAGCUGCCACAGGUUCUUUCUGCGUAUAGUUGCCCCAGCUUGAGCUGCAUGCAUUGAAGGAAAUGGCCCAUGGCUGACUGAGUGAGGUGGGCUUUGUGGGAAAAGCUGCGUAAUCCAGGUGGUCCUUGUCGGGUGGGGCUGCCUGACCCAGGCAGGGUCUCCCUGGGGAUGUAGGAAGGUGAAAUGUGAACAGAGAAAGGAGUUCCUCCAGCACAUGUGUUCUAAAGCACCAGCGUCCCCUCCGUGAGUCCCUCCUCUCCACGGGAACGCUGGAAACCCCCAGAAACUGGCUGCCAAGACAUUUCCUGUGUUUCCUGACAUCUUUAGGUAGCAUAAUAGCAAACUUGAACCUGCCAAGGCCAUGAUAAAACUGCAAGCAAGAACAUUUAUCGUGGCCAGGUGCAGUGGCUCACGCCUGUAAUCCCAGCACUUUUGGAGGUUGAGGCGGGUGAAUCACCUGAGGUCAGGAGUUCGAGACCAGUCUGGUCAACAUGGUGAAACCCCAUCUUUACUAAAAAUACAAAAAUUAGCCAGGCAUGGUGGUGCAUGCCUGCAAUCCCAGCUACUCAGGAGGCUGAGGCAGGAGAAUCACUUGAACCUGGGAGGCAGAGGUUCCGAUGAGCUGAGAUCGGGCCACUGCAUUCCAGUCUGGGUGAGAGAGUUAAAACAGGAAUUAAAAGAAAUUAAAGAAUGUGUAAGCAAAAACUCAGUUGUAUGUAAGAAAACCCCAUUCACCCUGAGGAAGAGAAAGAGCUAAAGUCCUUUAAAAAUUAACUGCCUGUUUUUCUGUGGAUAGUGAGCCUUAUCUCUCUCCCUUUCCCAGGCAUUGUGAAGACCCUGUUUCUCUAGCUGUGCAGCUGCAAGGUCACUAGGCAGAUAAACUCAAGUCAUAAAACAUGUUUUUCCUUGAAAAGUAAAAAAUGAUGUAAUGCAUGUCUCAACUGAAUAACUGUCUUUGUUUCUUGCUUCUGUAAUAUGCUUCCCCCUGCACAGAUCUCCCCCUGCCCCACAAAAUGCUUAAAAGGUAACCGGAGCCGGGCGUGGUGGCUCACGCCUGUAAUCCCAGCACUUUGGGAGGCUGAGGCAGGCGGAUCAUGAGGUCAGGAGAUCGAGACCGUCCUGGUUAACAUGUUGAAACCCCGUCUCUACUAAAAAUACAAAAAAUUAGCCGGGCGUGGUGGCAGGCACCUGUAGUCCCAGCUACUUGGGAGGCUGAGGCAGGAGAAUGGCCUGAACCCGGGAGGCGGAGCUUGCAGUGAGCCGAGAUGGCGCCACUACACUCCAGCCUGGGUGACAGAGCGAGACUCCGCCUCAAAAAAAAAAAAAAAAAAAGGUAACCGGACUCUUUGUUCAGGGCUCAGUCUUUUUGGAUGUUAAUCUGACCGGGCCAGUGCACCUAACUAAAUAAUAAAUAAUAAGUAUCCUCCUCAACCUCUUGGUCUCUCUGAUUCCUAAAUUAUCCCACUGCAGAAUGAGACUCUGUCUCAAAGGAAAAAAAAGAAAAUUUAUUGAGACCUUAUUAUGCGUCAAUAGCUCUCUAUUCAGAAUCUCACUGAUCUUCGCAACCCUGGAUCUCACAACAACGAGAGCCCCACUAGGUUGCCUCUUUUGUUUUGUUUUGUUUUUUUUUUGAGAUGGAGUCUCACUGUCUCCCAGGCUGGAGUGCAGUGGCGUGAUCUCGGCUCACUGCAACCUCCGCCCUCUGGGUUCACGCCAUUCUCCUGCCUCAGCCUCCCAAGUAGCUGGGACUACAGGCGCCCGCCACCAUGCCUGGUUAAUUUUUUUGUAUUUUUAGUAGAGACGGGGUUUCACCAUGUUUGCCAGGAUGGUCUCCAUCUCCUGACCUCGUGAUCCGCCCGCCUCGGCCUCCCAAAGUGCUGGGAUUACAGGCGUGAGCCACCGCGUCCGGCUUAGGUUGCCUCUUAUACUGGGUUCACGCAUCCCCUGGGUGCAUGACAGUCUGACCACAAAGGACCCCGGUCCACAGAAGCAUGAUGCAUCUUGGAGUAUCGACUUUAUGCCAAUAUUCUUCUUCUUGAUACUGGUGGUGGUGAGAAAGUUGGGUAAUUUAACCAAAAGUAAAAAUCAAGAUGUCACGUUCCCAUUAAAACAAACAUAGAGUACA